GUGCCGAACCCACGGCCAGGCUUCCGUGGCCAGCAGCCCUAGAGGAAUGGCCAUCCUGUCCCUGCGAGCCCCUGGGCCCUGGCAGGCGAUGCAGCCCGGAGGAGAGCUGGUAGCCUAGAGUACAGCUGCUGGGCAGAACGGAGGUGUCCCUGCCAGCGUGCCUUCCUUGACGCUCCUCUGGCCAUGUUUUAAACACCAGGAGGUUUCCAGCGGCUUCCCCAGGCGUAGCUCCUGCACCUUUUUCCUGGGCUGGUCACCAUAUGUGAUGACAGUGCCAGUCUGUUCUGAGCAGCUCUGGGCUCCUGGCUUCACUGACAUCAUAAACAAGUCCUUAGCCCUUCCAUCCACCCCAGAAAGUAGGUGUUCCCCCUGAUUUAUAGGCAAGACAAUGGAGAACCAGAGUCUAAAUCAGGGCUGAUUUUUUUUUUUUUUUUGAGAUGGAGUUUUGCUGUGUUGCCUAGGCUGGAGUGCAGUGGCACAAUCUCGGCUCACUGCAACCUCCACCUCCCGUGUUCAAGUGAUUCUCCUGCCUCAGCUUCCCAAGUAGCUGGAUUACAGGCAUGCACCACCAUGCCCAGCUAAUUUGUUUGUGUUUUUAGUACAGACGGGGUUUCACCAUGUUGGUCAGGCUGGUUUGAACUCUUGACCUCAAAUGAUCCACCCGCCUCAGCCUCCCAAAGUGAGCCACCACACACCGGCCAUGAUUCUUAAAAAUAACAGUAAUAGGCCAGGCAUGGUAGCUCACACCUAUAAUCCCAGCAAUUUGGGAGGCAGAGGCAGGAGGGUUGCUUGAAGCCAGGAGUUUGAGACCAGCCUGGGCAUCAGAGUGAGACUCCGUCUCUACAAAAAGUUAAAAAAAAUUAGCUGAGUGUGGUGGCACACACUGGAGUUCCAGCUACUUGGGAGGCUAAUAUGGGAGGACCCCUUCAGCCCAGGAGUUUGAGGCUGCAGUGAGCUGUGAUCGCACCACUGCACUCCAGCUCGGGUGACAGAGCAACACCCUGUCUCAAAAAAAAGUAAUAAUGAUAAAUUAUAAUCAAUAUUUAUUGGGUGCUUACUAUGUGCCGGCCAGUGUUCUCUGAACUUAGUAUUAACUACUUUAAUCUUGACAAUAACCCUGUAUGGUACUAUUGUAAUCCCCAUUUGAGACAUGGGAGAAUGGAGGCAGAGAAACGUUUAUCCACUUACCCAAGGUCACACAGCUAGGAGCUAGCAGAGUUGGGAUUCAAGCUGGACGUGUCUGUCUUGUUACCAUGAAACUAUUGGGAUCAUCAGUCAGAAUCUUUUCUUUUUUUUUUUUCUGAGAUGGAGUCUCACUCUGUCACCCAAGCUGGAGUGCAGUGGCUCAAUCUCGGCUCACCUCCUGGGUUCAAGCGAUUCUCCUGCCUCAGCCUCCCAAGUAGCUGGGAUUACAGAUGCCCACCACCACGCCCGGCUAAUUUUUGUAUUUUUGGUAGAGACGGGGUUUCACCAGGUUGGCCAGGCUGGUCUCGAACUGCUCACCUCAGGUGAUCAGCCCACUUCUGCUUCCCAAAGUGCUGGGAUUACAGGCGUGAGCCACCGAGCUGGGUCUUUCAGUCAGAAUCUACUUUGGCCGCAAGAGACAAAAACCUCCCCUAUAACACUGGUGGGAAUAUCGUAUUUCUCUCACUUGAAUGAAGUCUGGCUGUGAGCAGCUUAGGGCUCAGGUGCAGUCCCCUGCAAUCACGUCACUCUCCCCAGUGUGGCUAUUCCAGCUGCAGCCUUUACAUCUGCAUUCCAGGCAGCAGGAGGCAGGGAUGGCUGAAGAGGGGCAGCCCCUACCUUUAAGGACAAUUCUCAGAAGUCUUUUCUUUUUUCUCAUAUGUAUGUAUACACACACACACAUAUAUAUGUAUAUACACACACAUACAUAUUUAUGUAAAAAAGAUUUUUUUUUUUUUUGAUAUGGAGUCUCGCUCUGUUGCCCAGGCUGGAGUGCAGUGGUGCGUUCUCGGCUCACUGCAAGCUCCGCUUCCUGGGUUCACGCUAUUCUGCUGCCUCAGCCUCCCGAGUAGCUGGGGCUACAGGCGCCUGCCACCACACCUGGCUAAUUUUUUGUAUUUCUAGUAGAGACAGGGUUUCAAUGUGUUAGCCAGGAUGGUUUCGAUCUCCUGACCUGGUGAUCCGCCCGCCUCGGCCUCCCAAUGUGCUGGGAUUACAGGCGUGAGCCACGGCGCCCAGCCCAUAUUUGUAUAAAAUUUAAUAGAGAUAGGGCCUCAUUGCAUUGGGCCUGGCCGGAUGCCGUCCUCCUGCCUUGGCCUUCCAGAGUGCUGGGAUUAUAGGUGUGAGCUACCACGCCCGGCCCAUUACUGUUGUUUUCAGAUAGCCCUGAUUUAGUCUCUGGUUCUCCCUUUUCUUGCCUAUAAAUCAGGGAGAACACGUACUUCCUGGGGUGGAUGGAAGGGCUAAGCACUUGGGUAUGUCAGUGAAGCCAGGAGCCCAGAGCUGCUCAGAUCUGCCUGAUCUUCUCAAGCCGAGGGGGUCAGAACAGUCACUUUACCAGGUCUAGCUGCUGGGGAGGCUGGGAAAUUAUGUGACAAACAAAAAUGAGGCUCCUCAUUCAGGAAGAAGGAGGAGUGAUGUUGGGAUGGCCUGAUUUCUCCUGUGUCCUGGGUGCUCCCUGGGAGACUGGGGAGGUGCUGGCAUCGGGUGGCCGCCUCUGACUCUGUGACCCACCCACAGUCAUCAGGUGGGAUGCUAUGGAAUAUGAUGAGAAGCUGGCCCGUUUCCGGCAGGCCCACCUCAACCCCUUCAACAAGCAGUCUGGGCCGAGACAGCAUGAGCAGGGCCCUGGGGAGGAGGUCCCGGACGUCACUCCUGAAGAGGCCCUGCCUGAGCUGCCCCCUGGGGAGCCGGAAUUCCGCUGCCCUGAACGCGUGAUGGAUCUCGGCCUGUCUGAGGACCACUUCUCCCGCCCUGUGGGUCUGUUCCUGGCCUCUGACGUCCAGCAGCUGCGGCAGGCGAUCGAGGAGUGCAAGCAGGUGAUUCUGGAGCUGCCCGAGCAGUCGGAGAAGCAGAAGGAUGCCGUGGUGCGACUCAUCCACCUCCGGCUGAAGCUCCAGGAGCUGAAGGACCCCAAUGAGGAUGAGCCAAACAUCCGAGUGCUCCUUGAGCACCGCUUUUACAAGGAGAAGAGCAAGAGCGUCAAGCAGACCUGUGACAAGUGUAACACCAUCAUCUGGGGGCUCAUUCAGACCUGGUACACCUGCACAGGGUGUUAUUACCGCUGUCACAGUAAGUGCUUGAACCUCAUCUCCAAGCCCUGUGUGAGCUCCAAAGUCAGCCACCAAGCUGAAUACGAACUGAACAUCUGCCCUGAGACAGGGCUGGACAGCCAGGAUUACCGCUGUGCCGAGUGCCGGGCGCCCAUCUCUCUGCGGGGUGUGCCCAGUGAGGCCAGGCAGUGCGACUACACCGGCCAGUACUACUGCAGCCACUGCCACUGGAACGACCUGGCUGUGAUCCCUGCACGCGUUGUACACAACUGGGACUUUGAGCCUCGAAAGGUUUCUCGCUGCAGCAUGCGCUACCUGGCGCUGAUGGUGUCUCGGCCCGUACUCAGGCUCCGGGAGAUCAACCCUCUGCUGUUCAGCUACGUGGAGGAGCUGGUGGAGAUUCGCAAGCUGCGCCAGGACAUCCUGCUCAUGAAGCCGUACUUCAUCACCUGCAGGGAGGCCAUGGAGGCUCGUCUGCUGCUGCAGGUCAGACUGCCAGCAGGACUGGCCCCCGAUGGGAAGCGCAGCCAGGGUGGUGAGGCACCUCAGGCUCAGGUUUUUUCCGGACAGCUUGUGCGUGGAGUGCCUUUAGCAGAGGGUCGCCUCACCACGGUCCCAAGGAACAAAGCAAACAGGUGUUCUGCCUACAAAAGAGUUCUCCAGUCAGUUCCGUUUGGCAAACCCUGCAGCCCUUAUGUGAAUCUCCAUGGGGUGGGUCCAGCCCAGCCCUCGUCAGGCAGGUUGACCACAAAACACAGUUUUCAAGGUUCAUCUAAUUAUGUGCUCAACAGAUACAGAUGUUCUAGAUUCUGGAACAGUGAACGAAACAGACAGGAAUGCUUGCCCUUAGUGCCUUUCAAGUAGGGAAGACAAGAAAAAUACGUUGUGUGCUGGGGUGGUGAACUCUGUGACAAGAUAGAGAAGGAAGGGUGGGGAAUGUGGGAAGCGUGG